UGAGCUUUCUUCUUUAUUUUUUUUAAGAAGGAUGUUCAGAUGGUUAAGUUGGGUUCCUAAAUUUGAAAAAUAUGUUGCAGCUGGGGAGGUAAAAUCAUUAACUUGUGCAAAUGACAAACAACUCAUAUCAAAGAUACAUUUUAAAAAGCAUAAAACGAUACUGUUAAACCAAUUCGAGAAAAAUUUGUUAUUAUGUGAAAAGUGUAUGAUCCAAAAGCAUUCUCACAUGCUUUACUUCUACGUCAGCACCUGAGUUACUGUUAAGCUAUGCAGAUAUGCAGACAAAAUAUCUUUAUCUGGCAAACAACAAGAAAGACACUGACUGCUGAAGCACUCUUGCAAACAACGCACCGGGAGAUCGUGGUGCUUUUCCCCUCAGUUACUAACUUGUUUCCUGAAAAAUAAGAAGCAAAGAGGCAGACUAUGAAAACUUCAGGAAUUAUAGAAUAUUAAAAACUAUAAGCUUCAGGGCCGGACAAGGUGGCUCACGCCUGUAAUCCCAGCACUUUAGGAGGCUGAGGCGGGCGGAUCACGAGGUCAGGAGUUUGAGACCAGCCUGACCAACAUGAUGAAACCCCAGCUGUACUUAAAAUACAAAAAUCAGCUGCGUCUGGUAGCAGGCGCCUGUAAUCCCAGCUACUCGGGAGGCUGAGGCAGGAGAAUCGCUUGAACCCGGGAGGCAGAGGUUGCAGUGAGCCGACACUGCGCCACUGCACUCCAGCCUGGGCGACAGAGUGAGACUCUGUCUCAAUAAAUAAAUAAAUAAAUAAAUAGGCACUGGGUAGAAAUACUGAGCUCUGGAAAUCAGGAAAAGGGAUGGACAUAUUGAAAACCAACUGUGGCAAAUUAGCCAAUGAACCUUUCCGACAGCCUCGUGUGCUGGGCAUUGGCGGGGAGGCACCUCGGGCGGGAUCAGGGCCUCCGUCUCGCGCACCGCCAGCGUGAACACCUGGUCCAUCCUCCGCUGGAUCUUGGCCGUGACCCCCGGGAACGGGCAGGGCCCCUCGCGGGCCCGCGCCAUCAGCACCUGGCGCUCGGAGUCCCGGUCGGCCUGGGUGCCCACCAGCACCAGCAGGACGGCCCCGGGUUCCCACAGCCCGCGCAGGCGCUCGCGCAGCGGCCUCACGGCCGGGAACGAGGCCUCGCUGCACACGCCCCGGAGCACCGCGAAGCCGUCGCCGUGGCGGAUGUCCAGGUCCUGGAGCGUGACCAGGUGCUCGGCGUCCGCCGCGUCCACGAUUUCCAGCAGCGCGGGCGCCGCGUUUGCCUCGAUCUCCUCGCGGAGCCGCUCCUCCGCCCACGCCGCGCACUGCUCGGGGAGCGGCCGCACGCGAACUGCGUGUCCAGCGUGGUCCUGCCCACGUCACGCUCCCCAGCAGCACACCCCGGCAGCCCUGGCGGGGCGCGGGACCAGCCCGCAGUGUCCGGGACGCGGCGGGGAGGGGAGGAGAGGGAGGAAGGGGAGGGGAAGGAGGAAGGGGAAGGGGCCUGGGAGCGCAGGGAACGGCGUACCAGGACUGUCCGGGCAGGGGCAGGGAGGGGAGAGGAGGGAGGGGAUGGGGGAGGGCAAGAGAGGAGAAAAGAGGAGGAGGGGAGGGGAGGAGAGACGAGGGGUCAGGGCGUGGCGGGGCUGGCGAGUCCUGUGGCGCGGGGGAGGGGCGGGCGUCUCCUGGACUUGCUUCCACCCGGCUUAAUCCCGCCCGGGGCGGCUCCAACUCCACUGUCGCGCUGUUCUCGGACCAAACUGAGAGUGGGGCGGCUAUUUCUCGGGGCCCAAUGACGAGAUGCAGAUGAACUGAGGAGGAAGAGCGUUUUUAUUUUCUGCAACUGGUUACAGGGAGAAAGGCCUGGAAAUGAUCACCGGACCAACUCAAAAUUACAGUUUUCCAGAACUUACAUACCUUCUAAGCGGUAUGUCUACGUGUAAGUGUGCAUGCAUCUGAAGACAUUAGUGAUGAACUUACGGUCAUCUGUGAGUCCUGAAGACCUUCCUCUGGAGCCUCAAUAAGGGCCUUGCUGUGUCACCCAGGCUGGAGUGCAGUGGUGUGAUCAUAGCUCACUGUGAGGCAGGAAAUUAAGGAAAGAAAGAAUAAUAAAAUUUUAAAAAGAGAAAAAUAAGCUUUCUAUAUUAGGCUGACUCAUCCCAAAGGCAGUAACAGACAAAGCCCAGACCCAGACGAAGUCUUGAUAACAUCAUCAAAGAAGCAGAGGCUCAAAGGAGUGUGCUCUGGAGACUCUCCCAGCACUCCCUCAACAUAAGGAUAAGAAAAAGUUCCCCCUCGAACCCCAACCCCCUCCAUGUGAUUGUACCUUGCUCUGCAAGUUUUAUGAAUUUAUAGAUUCUUGUUUUCUGUAACUAGAAACUUCAAGUAUUCUGUUUUAUCUAAGCAGCACAGUGAAGGUUAUACAACAUGCCUGAGCAGGCCUGGGCUGCGGCCUUCUGGGCCCCAUAGCGAAGGUUAUGAGAUAAGCCUGUGCAAGGCUCUUUUAAGCAAGCCUAGAUAACAGCCAUCUGGACUGCAUAGCAAGAAUUACAUGUAACCCUGGGUUAUGCACCUGUCACAAUUUGAUUAACUGCCUAUGUUCUGUCUCUGUAUCCUUGCUUUCAUGCCACUGUAAGCUUGUUUCAAACUAGCCCACUCCCGUUCAAAGGUGUGUAUAUGAGUCAAGUGCUGUCUUUGUUCUGGGCCCAGUUUUUGGAUGUUAAUCCACUGGGUCUGAGUGCACUCAAUAAAAUUCUCAUGUCCCACCUA